GCCGAGGUGGGCGCCGAGAGCUGGGCGCCACAGCCCGCGCGUCCCGCUGCGCCCCGCGCGCCCCGGGGUCUAUGGAGCUGCCCCUCCGCGCCGCCCGGCCGGCCCCACGCCGCGCCCGGAGCCUGCUCUGCGGCCAAGUAAUCGGACUGGCGGUCCUGCGGGAGACUCGGGGCUCGGAGCCCGCCUGAGCGAGCCCCCCGGAGAUGGCGGCCCCCUAUCCCGGCAGUGGCGGCGGAAGCGAGGUCAAAUGCGUGGGAGGCCGCGGCGCCAGCGUCCCCUGGGACUUUCUACCCGGGCUGAUGGUCAAGGCGCCGUCCGGACCGUGCCUGCAGGCGCAGCGCAAGGAGAAGUCCCGGAACGCGGCGCGCUCGCGGCGCGGGAAGGAGAACCUGGAGUUCUUCGAGCUGGCCAAGCUUCUCCCGCUGCCCGGCGCCAUCUCCAGCCAGCUGGACAAGGCUUCCAUCGUGCGCCUCAGCGUCACCUACCUCCGCCUGCGCCGGUUCGCCGCGCUGGGGGCGCCGCCCUGGGGGCUGAGAGCCGCGGGGCCGCCAGCUGGCCUCGCCCCAGGCCGCCGCGGCCCCGCAGCGCUGGUCUCCGAAGUCUUCGAGCAGCACCUGGGAGGUCACAUCUUGCAGUCCCUGGAUGGCUUUGUGUUCGCCUUGAACCAGGAAGGAAAAUUCCUCUACAUCUCAGAGACAGUCUCCAUCUAUCUGGGUCUCUCACAGGUGGAGAUGACGGGCAGCAGCGUCUUCGACUACAUUCACCCUGGGGACCACUCAGAGGUGCUGGAGCAACUGGGGCUGCGGACGCCGACGCCCGGCCCCCCAACCCCGCCCUCCGUCUCCUCUUCCUCCUCCUCUUCCUCUUCGCUUGCAGAUACCCCCGAGAUCGAGGCCAGCCUCACCAAGGUGCCCCCCUCCUCCCUGGUCCAGGAGCGCUCCUUCUUUGUCCGCAUGAAAUCCACGCUCACCAAGAGGGGGCUGCACGUCAAGGCCUCAGGGUACAAGGUCAUCCACGUGACUGGGCGCCUUCGGGCCCACGCCCUGGGCCUUGUGGCCCUCGGGCACACGUUGCCCCCGGCCCCCCUGGCUGAGCUGCCACUCCAUGGACACAUGAUCGUCUUCCGUCUCAGCCUGGGUCUCACCAUCCUUGCUUGUGAGAGCAGAGUCAGCGACCACAUGGACCUGGGGCCCUCAGAGCUGGUGGGCCGCAGCUGCUACCAGUUUGUCCACGGACAGGACGCCACGAGGAUCCGCCAGAGCCACGUGGACUGUGAGACCCACCUCCACCCACCAAGCCUGCCUACCACCCCCCAGACCCGAGCAUCCCACUCCCUGGUCCCUGGAAGUCCUUCUUCAGGGCUGCCCACAGUCCCUCCUGCUGCACCUACAGCUCCAGGGACUCCGUUUAGCAUUGGAAGAGCAGCAAGGAGACUGAGUGAUGCCUCAGGAUUGCUGGACAAGGGUCAGGUGAUGACUGGUUACUACCGUUGGCUGCAGCGUGCCGGGGGCUUCGUGUGGCUGCAGUCUGUGGCCACAGUGGCUGGGAGCGGGAAGAGCCCCGGGGAGCACCAUGUGCUUUGGGUCAGCCACGUGCUCAGCCAAGCCGAGGGUGGCCAAACUCCUUUGGAUGCCUUCCAGCUUCCAGCCAGCGUGGCCUGUGAGGAGGCAUCCAGCCCGGGGCCAGAGCCCACAGAGCCGGAGCCUCCGACGGAAGGGAAGCAGGCUGCCCCAGCGGAGAACGAGGCCCCCCAGACCCAGGGCAAACGCAUCAAAGUGGAGCCCGGCCCGAGGGAAACCAAAGGCUCCGAGGACAGUGGCGACGAGGAUCCCUCCAGCCACCCGGCCACACCGAGGCCCGAGUUCACCUCUGUCAUCCGGGCAGGGGUCCUGAAGCAGGAUCCGGUGCGGCCAUGGGGCCUGGCGCCUCCCGGGGACCCCCCGCCCACCCUCCUGCACGCGGGCUUCCUGCCGCCGGUGGUGCGGGGCCUGUGCACACCCGGCACCAUCCGCUACGGCCCCGCGGAGCUGGGCCUGGUGUACCCGCACCUGCAGAGGCUGGGUCCGGGCCCCGCGCUCCCGGAGGCCUUUUACCCGCCCCUGGGCCUGCCCUACCCGGGGCCCGCGGGCACCAGGCUGCCGCGGAAGGGGGACUGAGGACUGGCAGAGCUGCCGGCGCCGGACCCUGCGACAACCGGGGUCCCCCAGGACAGUAGGCCCGGCUCUGCCCGUAGCCCUGAGAAUUAAACGCCGGCUCUCCCUGCAGUGGUUUGGGCUCCGG